AAAGAGAGAGAGACAGCAGGAAGGAGAAGGGAGGCAUCAGGACAGGAGGCAGGUGGAGCUAAGGACAGGGAUGUAGACAGAGGAGAGGAAAGAGACAGACAGUGGAUCUUCCUGUCGUGGGAGCCCCUAAGGGGGUUGGGGGAAGCUUGCACCUAGAUUCCUGAGGACAUUCCUGGGCUGGGCAAGGGUCCCUCCACUCUUCCUGGCCAGAAGCAGGUUUGCUGCCCCUCAUUAUUUAGAGAGGUCUGGACUUUCUGAGGCUUUCUACUUGCUCAGCUCGUGGUGCUGGGGACCAACACAGAGAAGUGACCCAUUUAGGGCCACACCACCAGGGUCUGACCCUAGUAUUCCCAAUCCAGCAUUCAUUCUCUUCCCCGGGCCCUGGGCCUCUCACCACCAUUUCAGGCUCCUAUCUGCCUUUGGAGCAGGCUGUGUGGCCAGGCAGCGUGAAGAGACUUGAAUUACAGCCAGAGGGAUGGAGGUCACCCAGCCAGUGAGAACCCCAGUGCCUGGCCCCUGCCUGGCAGGUACAACCCAGAGGCCUCUGGGGCCAGCUCUCUUCUCUGAACUAGUCCUGUUGGACACCAGGAAGGGCCUGGCAUGACCUUCCCCUCCAGGUCACAGCUAGGCUUUGGCCUUGAAUGGAGCCACAGAAGCCAGGUGGGUAGCUCUAGGGAUUGGAGGUAGAGGAGGAGAUGGGGGCUCAGAGGCGCAGCCCAUGGCUUUCCCGGGGUCACAAUCUCAGGGCCCUGCCGUGAAGCCAGGUGUGUCCUCCUCCUAUUCUGCCUUGGGGUCAACCCAGCCUGGCAAGGGGCAGACUGCUGACCUGUGGACACGAGGGAAAGUUCCAGAUGCCUGCCACAUCAGGAAAAUGCUGGAGGCAGAGAGAGGUCAGGAACAUUCAUUUUUAUUGGGAGGUCAGUUCUGGCUAGAUGUUCCUUUCUGGCAGGACACUUUGAGUCAUUUCCGUCCUCCCAGUACAUGGCACAGGGCUGGCCCUCAAAAGAUGCUUGGGAAGUGUUUGCUGCCUAAAUGAAUGAAUGGGUGGGUAAGAAGCAAGGCCUGGGCUUUACUCAUCUCAGUGUUGUUCUGCCCAAUGCUGGCCUCCUGAUUUGCGCUCCUUGAAUGUUUAUGGGAUGAAUAAGUGGCCUCUGGGAGCCCUUCCCCUCCUCUCACCCCUUCCUUCUGUGAUCCCAGCCCCUCCCACAGUAGAAUCAAAAUGGAUUUGGGCCCUGGGGAGAAGCAGACCCUUGCUUCCAUCCCUCCCUGCCCAGUUGACUGGGAGCUGAGGGCUGACGGGCCCCCAACCACGAUGGAGCUGCUGUACAGUGUGGGGCUGAGGGACUGACUGGCAUUGGCAUCCUUGGGCUCUGCUAUCUAAAAGCUAUGUGACCUUGCACAGAUGGCCUUCCCUCUUUGUGGCCAUUUCCUAAGCUGUGAAAUGGAGCCACAGAGGCCACGAGGAGGAGGCGCAUGGGCUUGGUACAGAGGGCAGUCAAUACAUGCUCACCACCGUUAAGAGCCCAAAUUGCAUGUUGCUCUUUCAGAGCUUCCCCUCCCACUGGCCCGUGGGCUCCCUGACGCCCCCUGCAGCCAGACAGGCGAGGGCGAGAUGACAAAAGGCAAGCAGGGCCCAAGCCCCCAAAUCCCUGUUCUUUUCAUAAAAACAGAGACAGCCUCCUCCCAUUCAUUGUUCUGCUAAGGCGAGCAUCACAGACUCAAUUCCUCCUCGGACCUGAAAAGUUCCUUCCUUCCUUUCCCCUCCCCUGUCACAUUUCCUUUAUCUAAAUCCUCAGCUAUGAAAGGACACAUCGACAGCUGGGGGCGUUAUCUGGUGGAGGGGACCUUUUCCUCGGGUGUCUCCGAGAUAAGGCGUCUUAUCAGCCCCCAUGUCAGGGAAGGUGCCAAGCAUUCUAAUCAUUGAGGCAUGCGACGUUUUUCCCCUCCCUGCCCCCCCUUUUUUUAUUAAAGUCACAAAAGACCUUGAGCUUAUAAACAGUCUGAUUUGCAGAUAGGGUUUCAAAAUGAACAGUGCUCCCUGGAUGGUGCUUGGCCAGGGGGGUAAUGAGUCCAGGCGGGGACUCUGAGAGGCUGGCCUCCUGCAGAUGGGAUGAUGCCAGGCAGGGAGGGGGCAAGAUGGGGUCACAGAAAGAACAUGAGUGUUUUAGGCACAUGCCCCAGUCCUGUCCCUGCCUUGCUGUGUGACCUUGUUUGGGACGCUUGGCUUCUCUGGGCCUAGAUCACUUUAUCUGACAAUAACCAAUUCAUUGAUUCGGCCAUUCAUUCAACACCUAUCUAGUAAAUGAUUACUCUUGCCAGGCACUGGGGAGAGACAGACAAAUAAGACACGGUCCCUACCCCUAAGAAACACAGUCCAGCGGAGGGAGAGAGAUGUGAAAAUUGGCAAUUACACCUUGGUGUGAUUAGAGCAGAGAUGGUGGAUAUCUAGAGGAAGGGAAGGGUGAGCCAGGGUCUGAAGACAGAUCUGAGUUCGAACGGAUCAGGGUCACGGUGCCGUAGGCAGGAGAACCAGCAGGGGCAGAGGUCUGGAGGUGUGAGGCAGCCUGGCUGGAAGGAGGGCCAGGGGGAGCCAAGAGGGAGAUGAGGUGUGGUGGGCAAAGAGGGCUGGGCUCCACGCCGGGGCCAGAGAGGUUUUAAGGCCAAGGAGGGGGAUUUGACCGUCUUGGUUGCAGAUGAUGGGGAUGAUGCAGGAGUUGGAGGUGGUGGUCCCCUCCCCACUUCCCUCCUAGGACACCCCACCACCCUGCCAUGUGCCCCCAGUGGCAGGACACAGGGUUCCUGGGAGAAUGGGCAGUGAGUUGGGAGAACUGGGGUUGCAGAGAGAAAAAAGUCCCUCCUCUUUAAGUGAAGAGCAUCUCUCAGGCUGCCUGUAGCCCUCCAGAAGCAAGGAAUGGGAGGAUGUAGGCAGCUGCCCUGGCAAAGCUGAGCCAAAGCUGAGGCCUACACUUGGACACCAUCACACCCUGAAAACCCCUCCCAGCUCCCAGAACUGCCUGGCAUCCACCAUAAGAGCACGCUGACAACUAGAGCCCUGCUGGGAAGGGAGCUGAUGGGGUCCCAGGAGGCUCCAGAAUAGGCGACCUGCCCCUUCCCCAACAAUUGCAGCCCCCAGCCCACCCUUUUUCAACUGCAAAGCAUGUGGGAUGUAUGGCCCAAGGGACAUUAGGGCACCUAGAGAAGGGCUGGACUUCUGGACCCCAGUAAAAGGCUGGAGAUAGGGCCGGGCAUGGCCAGGACUCUGGAAGAAAGUGACCUGGAGGUACCCACAGGGAUCAUGGAGCCACUGUUACAGGCCAGAGAGGGUCAUUAACCCAGCCGGGGUCACACAGGGUGUGCUGGGAGGCAAGGAGGUUCCAGCCUUCCAGCCCAGGUUUCCACAGGGCACCAGCCUCUGACCUCCCUCCUUACUGGCCUGGGUGCAGCCAAGCUCAGUGGUGAGGGGGUAAGUGCACCCAGCCACUCCCUGCCUGGCAGGCCACUGCUCCCUGUGGCUUGGGUUUCCCAUUUGUGGAGGGAGAGGUCUUGGACUGGCUUUCUCCGGAUCUCCCUCCUUUCCCCCAACCCCUAUGUCAGAGCGGCUAGAGAUGGACUCUGCCCUGGAGCAGGGGCCACAGAAAGAGGCUGGGGCAGGGUGAGGGAGGUUGCCACAGGCCUCUUACCUUCCAGAUUGCACAUGAUUGUGAGUCUCCAUAGACCAUCCGACUGUGCGUAAGAGGGUGCCUGUAAGUGCAGAGGAACAUGCCAUGCAGCAAACACAUAUGUACAUAGGGACCCAGUCGCAGAGCGCACCCCACUGGGGACCCCCAGCUCAGCCAUGCUGGCCUGUCUGCAGAGGACCCAGAACGCCCCGGGCCAACACCUGGCCUGCCCGAGCAAGAGCCUGGAGCUGCGCAAGUGCGAGGCGGUGGCCAGCGCCAUGCAUUCCUCCCGCUACCCGAGCCCAGCAGAACUGGACGCCUAUGCCGAGAAGGUGGCCAACAGCCCGCUGUCCAUCAAGAUCUUCCCCACCAACAUCCGUGUGCCCCAGCACAAGCACCUCAGCCGCACAGUCAAUGGCUAUGACACCAGUGGCCAGCGCUACAGCCCCUACCCACAGCACACCGCUGGCUACCAGGGCCUUCUGGCCAUUGUCAAGGCCGCGGUUUCCUCCUCCAGCACGGCCGCACCAGCUGGGCCCGCCAAAAGUGUGCUCAAGAGCGCCGAGGGCAAGCGGACCAAGCUGUCACCGGCCGCCGUGCAGGUGGGCAUUGCGCCCUACCCAGUGCCCAGCACUCUGGGUCCCUUGGCCUACCCCAAGCCACCUGAGGCGCCUGCUCCACCACCCGGCCUGCCCGCAGCCGCCACUGCCGCCUCCGUCAUCCCCCUGCCGGGCCGGGGCCUGCCCCUGCCACCUUCCAACCUGCCCUCCAUCCACAGCCUCCUGUACCAGCUCAACCAGCAGUGCCAGGCCCCGGGCGCCGCACCCCCUGCCUGCCAGGGCAUGGCUAUUCCCCAUCCCAGCCCUGCCAAGCACGGCCCAGUGCCCAGCUUCCCCAGCAUGGCCUACUCGGCUGCAGCCGGUCUGCCCGACUGCCGGAAAGGCACUGAGCUGGGCCAGGGAGCCACCCAAGCCUUGACGUUGGCUGGGGCCGCCAAGCCUGCAGGGUACGCAGACAGCGGCCUGGAUUACCUGCUGUGGCCGCAGAAACCGCCCCCACCGCCGCCCCAGCCACUGCGUGCCUACAGUGGGAGCACGGUGGCCAGCAAGUCCCCUGAGGCUUGCGGGGGCCGGGCAUACGAGCGGGCCAGCGGGUCACCCCUCAACUGUGGCGUGGGGCUGCCCACCAGCUUCACCGUAGGCCAGUACUUUGCGGCCCCGUGGAACAGUGUGCUGGUGACACCCACCAGCGACUGCUACAACCCAGCGGCGGCGGUGGUGGUCACGGAGCUGGGGCCGGGGGCAGCCCGGGAGCUGGCUGGGCCCCCUGCAGAUGCCCUCUCGGGCCUGCCCAGCAAGAGUGUGUGCAACACAUCGGUGCUGAGCAGCAGCCUGCAGUCACUGGAGUAUCUCAUCAACGACAUCCGGCCGCCCUGCAUCAAGGAGCAGAUGCUGGGCAAGGGCUAUGAGACGGUGGCCGUGCCCCGGCUACUCGACCACCAGCAUGCCCACAUCCGCCUACCCGUCUACAGAUAAGGCCUGCCCUGCGGACAUACGGACAUGCGGACAGGGCGCAGAGCCGGGAGGCAGGCCGCAGAACAGGGUGGGCGGCUCGCAGGGGCGCUCAGCCCCACCCUGUGCCUGCUGAUGCCCACAGGGGAGCCAGGCUGGCUGCCGCCUCGCUGUGGCCGGAUGGAGGGUGGCAGGGCAACCUCACAUACCAAGGCCCCUCCCCACCAUCGGUUGCCCCAGGACACAGUGAGGGCCUGGGGGCAGCCACUGACGCCCAUGCCUUCCUUUAUCUAAGCUGGCAGAGGCAGGGAGAGAGAAACCACUCAAAAACAGGAAUGGUUCUUUCUGGGCCUCCUGGGACAGGGGCCCAGGCCAAGGUGGGGUGCAGGAGGAAACAGGCGCACCAGAGUCAGGGUGGGGGCAGGGCAGCCCCCCCAGGGGUCAGGCAGCUGUGUCUCCCCACACUGGCUCCCCAGUAUUCUGGAAAAGGGGUACAGGAGGCCGAUAGGAAGUCACUGGGCCCAAAGUGUCUCCCCACCAGCCAGGUGAAGACCACUCUGACAGAGGCUCCAGGGACUAUACCAGUCCCCCUGUUCCUCCUUCCCCUACCCCCACCAUUCCUUCCUAACACAGAGUUGCACCCCCAUCCCCAUUCUCCAAACCCUGGACUACCAUAUUCCCCCUUCCCUCCAAUACAUCUUAUAGGGCUGCUGGGUACAGUUGUUCAGGCUGUGCACUGCACAAGGGCACCUUGUCCAAGGAGACACCACUUUCACCCAAACUUGUAUAUUUAUUACAAUUUUCUGCAUCUUGAGGAAGGGGCGUCAUUUUCCUGUUCGCACAAAGGCACCACAGGGGCUAACAGUGGGCCUGCAAUCUUAGAUCCCAUCCUUGCCUUCUUCGAGGGAUCUCUUGGGACCCUCCUGGUUUUAACUGGGAGGCCCAGACCAACUCCUUUCCUGCAAACCACCCUCCAAGGCCUGUCCCACACGAUCAAGGCAGGGAAAGAUAGGCAGGAGUCCCCUCACGAAGUCCUCAAGUCCUGGCCCCUCUGGCGCUCUGGAAGCGGUACUGUAUCUCUCUCCAAGGCCUGGUCAAGCACUAAGUGCAUUUACAAAUCUCUGAGAAUGUUUUUUUUAUACUAAAAUUGACCAUUAUAUUCUACUGUGAGAAGUGCAGUCUGCACUAUAUUGUUUUAAAAACGAAGAGAAAGAAGAAAAAGGAAAACACA